AGGUUUUUGAAGAUGGCGGCCCUCAAGGCUCUGGUGUCCGGCUGUGGGCGGCUUCUCCGUGGGCUACUAGCGGGCCCGGCAGCGACCAGCUGGUCUCGGCUUCCAGCUCGCGGGUUCAGGGAAGUGGUGGAGACCCAAGAAGGGAAGACAACUAUAAUUGAAGGCCGUAUCACAGCGACUCCCAAGGAGAGUCCAAAUCCUCCUAACCCCUCUGGCCAGUGCCCCAUCUGCCGUUGGAACCUGAAGCACAAGUAUAACUAUGACGAUGUUCUGCUGCUUAGCCAGUUCAUCCGGCCUCAUGGAGGCAUGCUGCCCCGAAAGAUCACAGGCCUAUGCCAGGAAGAACACCGCAAGAUCGAGGAGUGUGUGAAGAUGGCCCACCGAGCAGGUAGAAGGCCCUGGGGACCAAGAGGGGCAGAGGGCUGCAGGCACUCUCUCCCCACCCAGCUGCCCCAUGUUUCAGCCCCUCCUGGAAGAAAAGUGGAUAUCCGGAGUGUUAAUUAUACUCACCACCCAAUGCCAACCUUCCCGCUCCCUUGGGCUUUCCCUCUGGCCCCCUCAGAGCUGCAGAGGGAGCUGCAAAGACUAUCCCCUCUUCCCCGCCACUCAGGUCUAUUACCAAAUCACAGGCCUCGGCUUCCUGAAGGAGUUGUUCCGAAGAGCAAACCCCAACUCAACCGGUACCUGACGCGCUGGGCUCCUGGCUCCGUCAAGCCCAUCUACAAAAAAGGCCCCCGCUGGAACAGGGUGCGCAUGCCCGUGGGGUCACCCCUUCUGAGGGACAAUGUCUGCUACUCAAGAACACCUUGGAAGCUGUAUCACUGACAGAGAGCAGUGCUUCCAGAGUUCCUCCUGCACCUGUGCUGGGGAGUAGGAGGCCCACUCACAAGCCCUUGGCCACAACUAUACUCCUGUCCCACCCCACCACGAUGGCCUGGUCCCUCCAACAUGCAUGGACAGGGGACAGUGGGACUAACUUCAGUACCCUUGGCCUGCACAGUAGCAAUGCUGGGAGCUAGAGGCAGGCAGGGCAGUUGGGUCCCUUGCCAGCUGCUAUGGGGCUUAGGCCAUGCUCAGUGCUGGGGACAGGAGUUUUGCCCAACGCAGUGUCAUAAACUGGGUUCAUGGGCUUACCCAUUGGGUGUGCGCUCACUGCUUGGGAAGUGCAGGGGGUCCUGGGCACAUUGCCAGCUGGGUGCUGAGCAUUGAGUCACUGAUCUCUUGUGAUGGGGCCAAUGAGUCAAUUGAAUUCAUGGGCCAAACAGGUCCCAUCCUCUUCAUGACAGCUGUGAGCUCCUUACUGUGGGAGAGCUGCAGGGAGCCAAGGUGGGCUGCCUGACACACUUGCCGCUCUCGUGUGAAUCCAAGAAACUGCGUUCCUCAAA